UUGCUGCUGUUGUUGUUACCCCAGGUGCACAGAAUUGAGCUGAUUAUAUCCUUCGGUUUGUGGCCUUGUGCUAUUAUCAUUCUGGGCAAGAGCCCUAGCUGGUUUUAUUUUAUUAUCAGUCUCCAAUCCUUGCUUCAAUCCCUUGUAGACCUUCAUUUUAAUGUAUUUAAUGUGUGUUUAUCAAACUCAUUCUCCAUAUAUAUCUAUAUUUAGCUGUAUAUGUGGCAUUCAAAAAAGAAUGUAUAGUUGUGUAUGUGUGAAUGUGUUCUAUAUAGCAUAAACAUUUUUGUAUCAUAAACCUUAUUAUGUUUCUUACUACUUUCAUUCAAUGUUAGCUCUUGGGCAGCUUUCUAUGGUGCUAUAGAGACAUGCGUCUCUUAAUGAUGGGCAUAUGUCCUGAGAGAUGCAUCCUUAGGUGAUUUAAUCAUCAUGUGAGCAUCAUAGAGUAUACUUACACAAGCCUAGAUGGUAUGUGAUAUAGCCUAUUGCUCCUAGGCUACAAACAUUUACAGUAUGUUGCUGUGCUGAAUACUGUAGGUGAUUGUAACAUAAUGGUAUUUGUGUAUCUAAACAUACCUGAACAUGGAAACGAUAAUGCAUUGCGCUAUGAUGUUAUGAAGACUACCAUGUCGCUAGGCAAUAGGAAUUUUUCAGCUUCAUUACAGUCUCAUAGGACUACUAUCUAUAUGUCGUCCAUUGUGGAUUAAAACGUUUUUAUGCAGUGCAUGAACGUCUUUAAAUCUAGUUCAUUUCUUCCAAUUGCUGGCCACUUUGCCAUCGUUUAUGUGUAGUCAUGUGCCACAUGGUGGCAUUUUGAUCAGUGAUGGACAGCAUAUACAGCUGUGGUCCCAUAAGAUUAUAAAACUGAUGCCUACUGUACCUUUUCUAUGGUUAGAUGUGUUUAGAUAUACAAAUACUUACCACUGUGUUACAAUUGCCUACAGUAUUCAGUACAGUAACAUGCUGUACAGGUUUGUAGCCUAGGAGCAAUAGGCUAUGCCAUAUAGCCUAGCGUGUGGUAGGCUUUACCAUGUAGAUUUGUAUAAGUACACUCUGUGAUGUUUGCACAGUGACACAAUCACCUAACGACACACUUCUCAGAAUAUAUCCUCAUCAUUAAGUGAAGCAUGACUGUAUAUGAAUUGUUACUUAUCCAGUCUCCCAGCUGUGGACAUCUAAGUUGCCUCUAACUCCUUUCAUUCCAAACAACAUUUCAAUAAAUCGCACAUAUAUGUUUCCUUUGAACCUGUUAGGAAUUUUCUCAGGGGAAUAUUUCCAGGAGUACAGGAUUGCUCAGUGGUAAGUCACAUACAUUUGUAAAUCUACUGACUACUGUUGUCACACUUUCUCCUGAAUGAGUGCACCAAUUCACACCAGUUCAAUGUGCAAUACAGAAGGGAUUCUACUUUCCACAGUUUUAUCAGCACGUAGCAUCAUCCAAUCUAAUUAUCCAUAGAACAUUACCUUAAUGUUGCUUUUAUUUGUGUUUCACUGAUAAGUAUUGAAGCUGAGGAUCACUUUAUCUGUUUAGAGACAUUCAGAUUCUGCAUUCUGAGUCUAUUCAUAAACUUUGACUAUUUUCUAUUGAGUUUCCUGCUUUUUUAUUCAAUAAUUUGAGGAAACUCAUAAUAUAUUUGGGAUAAUAAUGCUUUGUCAAUUUUACAUGUUGUACAUAUCCCCUCCAAGUUUAUGGGGCUUGUUUUGUUUUUAUUGUAAAUACAAAUUGAACAUUGUAUAUGUAAUCACCAUGUUUAAGAACAUGAUAAUCCCAUUAUGUUGAUAGGCUAUAAUAUGCCAAAUCAUCCCUACCUCUUUUUUUACUUGAUUUUUAAGUUGAGUCUGGUUUUAUAUUUAUAUUAAAUUAUUUGUAUUAGAAGUUAUCAUUGCAAUAUUUCUCCUGUUGCUUGUCAAUUUUUCUUUUAUAUUUUUGUCUGUUUUUUGAGACAGGAUCUCACUCUGUCACCCAGGCUGGAGUGCAGUGAUGCCAGCCUCCUCCACCCCCAUCCAUCCACCCACCUUAUGCGGGGAUAAAUGAGUAGCUGGGACCACAGGUACACACCACCAGGCCCAGCUAUUAUUUUGUAUUUUUAGUAGAGACCUGGGUCUCGCCAUGUUGCUCAGAAUGGUUUGGAACCCCUGGGCUCAAGAGAUCCACUCACCUUGGCCUCACAACGUAUUGGGAUUACAGGCGUGAGCAAUAGCACCCAGCCUUCUUUUAUAUUUUCUAAAGACAAAUGCUAAGCCUGCAUUACUUGAUCAAAUCACACGACCAUUUUAAAUGAAUCUUAGUAUGCACUGCCAUAUUGCUUACCCAAGGAGUGUAUAUGCUUUUAUCACUAGCAACAAAAAUGGUCAGUUUAGUCAUAACCUUGAAAAAUUAUGUAGUUUUUAUCCCAUUGAUAGUUUAGUAACUAAUAAAUAAUAUAACAUACUAUAAUUUAUGCUUCUUAUAUAAAAUUUGAUAGCCUUCAUUUCAUUUAUCAAGGACCUUUGUAUCUUUUAUAAAUUUUAAUGAAUUAAUAAGCAAUAUUAAUAGAUGCUUACUCUGUCAAGCACUUGGCUGAAUUCUUUAUCAGUAAUACUUAAAUGAUACUACAAUAUAGACUCUAUUAUUGCUUCCUAUUGUAUAAAUGGAGAAACUCAGUCAACAGUAUUAACCUCUUAUUUCUCCCAAAUCUUAUUUUAUAUAUAGUUAGUAUCACAGAAUUUAGCCCUGACCUCUGCUUGAAACACGUUUGCUUUAUCUCUCUUGCUUUAAGCUAUUUGAGACUAGUGAGCAAAAAUGGUCCUCUUAUUUCAUGCCAUCAACAGUACCAGGUACUUCAAUUGUCACUUAAUAAGUAUUAUUUUAUUAAUUUCUAUCAAGUUUUCUACUUAUAAAUCCAUAAUAGAUCAUCAUACCUUGUAUUGUCUUCUUAUUUUCCUUCUUUCUCUUCUUUUUUAUGUGUCUUUAUUUGUCUCUUUAAUGUAUUUUCUCUUUCUCUCAAAGAAAAUUUAACUUAUCUCUGAAUAUAAGCAGGAGAUGGUAAAAGGAAAGAUAAAUUAUUGGCUAUAUUUGACAUUCAUAAGAGGCCAUACCUUUAGCCUUAUUUUGAAAUGAGGUUAUACACAUUUCCCCAACAAUACACUGACAGGCUUGAAAACAGAAUACAUUCAGCAUUCACUUUAAUUUUUAAUUGUGAACACUGAAACUAUGCCUUAGCUUAUCUGAUGAACCAUAGGAAUUUCUUCAUUUGGGGAAUUCCGUCCCCAAACCUGUAAGUAACCCUGGCUUCUCUGAAACUCUAUGACACCUUAGUAAAAAGUUAUUUUCAAUGCUUACAUUUACAAAAUACACCUGACAGUAUGUUUAUGAAGUCUCAGCACCACAAACUUUCUUCUCCCUCGGCAUCUAGGUCUUCCCGUCAUCAGCUCCUGUGUGGCUCUGCGUAUCUUACCACAAUAUAGAGUCACAUUCUUCUCUCCUUAGAUGGACAUAGAAAGAUAUACUUGGGGGUGAAAAUAUGGCCAGAAGAUGGCUACGAAAAGAAAUGCAGAAAAAAGAUUGUGCAGUGGUUACGUCUACUAGUGCCUGCUUUCAUCCUAGGGCCCAUAGCUACUAGGCCUUCGGUUGGGUUUUUGUUUGUUUGUUUUAACAGUUGUUAUUCAGAAUGGACUUUCUUUGGAAUGUGAGACUAAGGUGUGCGCCUAACGUCAUCAUAUUUUUUCUUUAGUAGUUUCUGCUCAGUAUCGCAAUAAAUUCUUCCAGGCUGAAUCUUUCUUCAUUUUCUUGCAAUACUGACAGAGAUGGGUAUUUUUACACCUCAGUGUCUUUUUGACCCACCUUUUAGCAGUCAUAAAUUACAAGAUGCUUAGAAUAUGAGACAGAAGAAGUAAGUUCCUAGACCAACCAGUUUGAGAAUGAGUCUGUACGUUUAACAGUGUCUGAGUGAUUUUGCGGUAAAUCAAUCAGGGACAUUAGAAUAAAUUACUUUCACUCCCAUCACUGGUGUGGAAUCAAGUCAAAUCCAGCAUGACCAAGUUAGGUAACAAAGGCAGAUGGACCAAAUAAGAGAACCUGAAAUUUGUCAAGGAACCUCACAUAUAUUUUCUUCUGACUUUUUGGUUUGCCACUCUGUCAUUACCUAAAGAAGGCAAAAGAAAGGUAAGCGUAGGAUAUAAAGCUUUUGGUGUUUAGAGCAAAUGAAUGUGUUAAACCCGGAGUUUAAGCUAACAGAUUCUUAUAACGGUAAUGAAUAUUUUAAGAGCCAUUUUUCAUCAAGCAUUUUCCAGAUAAGCUGUUACAAUCAAAGUUGCUGUUAUUAUGUGCUGCCAUCCGGUGUCCAUUUUGUAGAAUGCCAAGCUGAUGGCUUUGUUGAGUUUUUGUUUUUGUUUUUGUUUUGGGGGUGUUUUGUUGUUGUUGUUGUUGUUUGGGCUUUGAUUUUGUUUUUGUACUUCUAUUUGUCUGCUAGUUUUUUUUGCAUUUUUCCAACUUCACAAUUCAGGAUUUGCUUUAGGGAAGUUUUAUGAAGUGUUUCACUUGGAUAAAAUGUCCCACCAAUUGCAUAAAUGGUACAUAAAUGCCCUCAUAGAAAUUUAGUUCUCCCUACUUCCCAAUUGUAGUUAGCACCCCUUUUCCCCUUAGAUGUAAUUUGUUUUGUAUGUCAAAAGAUAAGAUAAAUACCUGCAUUUCUUUUUUUGUUUUGUUCUGUUUUGAGACUGAGUCUCGCUCUGUCACCCAGGCUGGAGUGCAGUGGCGCGAACUUGGCUCACUGCAGCCUCUGCCUCUCUAGUUCAAUUGAUUCUCCUGCCUCAGCCUCCCAAGUAGCUGGGAUUACAGACACCCACCACCAUGCCCAUCUAAUUUUCUGUUUUUAGUAUACUGGGUUUCGCCAUGUUGACCAAGUUGGUCUCAAACUCCUGACCUCAAGUGAUCAACCUGCCUCAGCCUCCCAAAGUGCUGGGAUUAUAGGUGUGAGCCACCGCACCUGGCCCAACACUUGGCAUUUCUUGCCCUAGGAUUUGUCUCCUGCAUGGAAUCACUAGGAUCAAACCCUUACCUGAUUGUUACCUGUAAAUUCCUGUGGAAACUGAUGGCUGUCUCCCUUACUCUUGGCACUUUGGACUGUCUUACUAAAGUUAGAUAUUUCCUGAACUGUGUGUCUUAGUUACCCCUUUAGUCUAUCCAACACCUUAAUUUUUGUCUCUCUGUGGAAAAAAUAGAAAACUAUUCUCUCAAAGUUAUGAUGAAAUGUGGAGGCACUGAUUGGUCAGUGGGUGAAUUUGCCUGCUGACCAUCAUGAUAGGGGUGGAAGACAGGGAUAAAGGGCUCGCAGUUCAGCAUUGCAGGAUGGCCCAGGUCAGGCUAAGACAUGGCUUUGCUCCAAAGAGAAAGAGAUUCUAGUACUUCCCUGACAAGUGUUCCUUAUCUCCCCCUCUUAGCUCCUCUCAUGAGGCUCUCAACUGGCAUGCUCAGAGUGACUACAGAGAGAGCUGCAUGCCACCUGCUGAGAGACCAUGGAGACACUGGAGUGAGCAGGGGCCUGAAUCCCAUCUCUAUGGCUUGUUUUCCCUUGGUUAGGAUGCAACCUUACUGGGCUUCAGUUUUCUCUUCUGUAAUAUGGGAGUAUCCUAGGCUCAUUCAGAAGACUUGGUUUCCAUGUUUAUUGUCCAUCUUCUUGUAGUUAGAAGUACAGUUUUUGAGGAAUGUCUUAUUUUCCAUCUCUUUUCAGCCCUUAGAAUUGUGUUUGGCACGUGGUAAAUGUUUAAUGGAGACAUGUGACCAGCUUAGUAAUUAAAUCACAUAGUGCAUAUAAAAUGCCAGGUGGCAUACCUGGAACAGAGCAGAAGCCAGUGCAAGCUCAGCGUGGGAAGCCCUCUGGAGAAAGCUCAGGAAAAACUGGUCUACUUCCUGGAUUGUUCUUUCUAGUCGAAGAAUUGAAUUUUACAAAGAAUCCAAGCAACAGGCUCUGUCCAAUAUGAAAACUGGGCACAAACCAGAAAGUGUGGAUUUGUGUGGAGCACACAUUGAAUGGGCCAAGGAAAAAUCGAGCAGAAAGAAUGUCUUUCAGAUCACAACAGUAUCAGGAAAUGAGUUCCUUCUACAGUCAGAUAUUGACUUCAUCAUAUUGGAUUGGUUCCACGCUAUCAAAAAUGCAAUUGACAGAUUGCCAAAGGAUUCAAGUUGUCCAUCAAGAAACCUGGAAUUAUUCAAAAUCCAAAGAUCCUCUAGCACUGAAUUGCUAAGUCACUACGACAGUGAUAUAAAAGAACAGAAACCAGAGCACAGAAAAUCUUUAAUGUUCAGACUGCAUCACAGUGCUUCCGAUACAAGCGACAAAAAUCGAGUUAAAAGCAGAUUAAAGAAGUUUAUUACCCGAAGACCUUCCCUGAAAACUCUGCAAGAAAAAGGACUUAUUAAAGAUCAAAUUUUUGGCUCUCAUCUGCACAAAGUGUGUGAACGUGAAAAUUCCACAGUUCCGUGGUUUGUAAAGCAAUGCAUUGAAGCUGUUGAGAAAAGAGGUCUAGAUGUUGAUGGAAUAUAUCGAGUUAGUGGCAAUCUGGCAACAAUACAGAAGUUAAGAUUUAUUGUCAACCAAGAAGAGAAGCUGAAUUUGGACGACAGCCAGUGGGAGGACAUCCACGUUGUCACCGGAGCACUGAAGAUGUUUUUCCGGGAGCUGCCUGAGCCGCUCUUCCCUUACAGUUUCUUUGAGCAGUUUGUGGAAGCGAUCAAAAAGCAAGACAACAACACAAGAAUUGAAGCUGUAAAAUCUCUUGUACAAAAACUCCCUCCGCCAAAUCGUGACACCAUGAAAGUCCUCUUUGGACAUCUAACUAAGAUAGUGGCCAAAGCCUCCAAGAACCUCAUGUCCACGCAAAGCUUGGGGAUUGUAUUUGGACCUACCCUUCUGCGAGCUGAAAAUGAAACAGGAAACAUGGCGAUCCACAUGGUCUACCAGAACCAGAUAGCUGAGCUCAUGCUGAGUGAGUACAGUAAGAUCUUCGGCUCAGAGGAAGACUGACAGACAAGACAAGCUACUGAAUACGUUCACAUCUGUCUUGAUGCCUAAUAUUUUUACAUUUCUGUAAACAUAUUUCUGAAAUAUUUUUUGCCUUUCAAGCGACAGAUGCCUCAUUUUGUGAAAACUUAAUGAUGAUUUUGUGUUUAAGUUCCAAACAUUUGAAUAAAAUAAUUGACAAUA